GCCUUCUGCCCGGGCGCUCGCAGCCGAGCGCGGCCGGGGAAGGGCUCUCCUCCCAGCGCCGAGCACUGGGCCCUGGCAGACGCCCCAAGAUUGUUGUGAGGAGUCUAGCCAGUUGGUGAGCGCUGUAAUCUGAACCAGCUGUGUCCAGACUGAGGCCCCAUUUGCAUUGUUUAACAUACUUAGAAAAUGAAGUGUUCAUUUUUAACAUUCCUCCUCCAAUUGGUUUAAUGCUGAAUUACUGAAGAGGGCUAAGCAAAACCAGGUGCUUGCGCUGAGGGCUCUGCAGUGGCUGGGAGGACCCCGGCGCUCUCCCCGUGUCCUCUCCACGACUCGCUCGGCCCCUCUGGAAUAAAACACCCGCGAGCCCCGAGGGCCCAGAGGAGGCCGACGUGCCCGAGCUCCUCCGGGGGUCCCGCCCGCGAGCUUUCUUCUCGCCUUCGCAUCUCCUCCUCGCGCGUCUUGGACAUGCCAGGAAUAAAAAGGAUACUCACUGUUACCAUUCUGGCUCUCUGUCUUCCAAGCCCUGGGAAUGCACAGGCACAGUGCACGAAUGGCUUUGACCUGGAUCGCCAGUCAGGACAGUGUUUAGCAUCUCUCUGACCAAUCAGCCUCUUCUUCUUCUACUUUUAAGAACUCCUGUGAAUAUAUCGGGCCCACCCAGAAAAUCCAGGAUAACCUCCCCAUCUCAAGAUAUUGAUGAAUGCCGAACCAUCCCCGAGGCCUGCCGAGGAGACAUGAUGUGUGUUAACCAAAAUGGCGGGUAUUUAUGCAUUCCCCGGACAAACCCUGUGUAUCGAGGGCCCUACUCGAACCCCUACUCGACCCCCUACUCAGGUCCGUACCCAGCAGCUGCCCCACCACUCUCAGCUCCAAACUAUCCCACGAUCUCCAGGCCUCUUAUAUGCCGCUUUGGAUACCAGAUGGAUGAAAGCAACCAAUGUGUGGAUGUGGACGAGUGUGCAACAGAUUCCCACCAGUGCAACCCCACCCAGAUCUGCAUCAAUACUGAAGGCGGGUACACCUGCUCCUGCACCGACGGAUAUUGGCUUCUGGAAGGCCAGUGCUUAGACAUUGAUGAAUGUCGCUAUGGUUACUGCCAGCAGCUCUGUGCGAAUGUUCCUGGAUCCUAUUCUUGUACAUGCAACCCUGGUUUUACCCUCAAUGAGGAUGGAAGGUCUUGCCAAGAUGUGAACGAGUGUGCCACCGAGAACCCCUGCGUGCAAACCUGCGUCAACACCUACGGCUCUUUCAUCUGCCGCUGUGACCCAGGAUAUGAACUUGAGGAAGAUGGCGUUCAUUGCAGUGAUAUGGACGAGUGCAGCUUCUCUGAGUUCCUCUGCCAACAUGAGUGUGUGAACCAGCCCGGCACAUACUUCUGCUCCUGCCCUCCAGGCUACAUCCUGCUGGAUGACAACCGAAGCUGCCAAGACAUCAACGAAUGUGAGCACAGGAACCACACGUGCAACCUGCAGCAGACGUGCUACAAUUUACAAGGGGGCUUCAAAUGCAUUGACCCCAUCCGCUGUGAGGAGCCUUAUCUGAGGAUCAGUGAUAACCGCUGUAUGUGUCCUGCUGAGAACCCUGGCUGCAGAGACCAGCCCUUUACCAUCUUGUACCGGGACAUGGACGUGGUGUCAGGACGCUCCGUUCCCGCUGACAUCUUCCAAAUGCAAGCCACGACCCGCUACCCUGGGGCCUAUUACAUUUUCCAGAUCAAAUCUGGGAAUGAGGGCAGAGAAUUUUACAUGCGGCGUGCAUUCAGCACCACUGCAUAUGAGGCUUCAAGUCAGGCACUGAGCGUUGAGAAACAAACAGGAUGUGGUCUCUGCCCUGGAGGAACCCACACACACCUUAGCGGAGAGGGGGAAAACAACCUAGCAAACACAACACAAAGUGGCGAUUCUCAAGUCAAGUCAAGACCCAUGGGAUGCAAACGGGCCCCAUCAGUGCCACCCUGGUGAUGACACGCCCCAUCAAAGGGCCCCGGGAAAUCCAGCUGGACUUGGAAAUGAUCACUGUCAACACUGUCAUCAACUUCAGAGGCAGCUCCGUGAUCCGACUGCGGAUAUAUGUGUCGCAGUACCCAUUCUGAGCCUCGGGCUGGAGCCUCCGACGCUGCCUCUCAUUGGCACCAAGGGACAGGAGAAGAGAGGAAAUAACAGAGAGAAUGAGAGCGACACAGACGUUAGGCAUUUCCUGCUGAACGUUUCCCCGAAGAGUCAGCCCCGACUUCCUGACUCUCACCUGUACUAUUGCAGACCUGUCACCCUGCAGGACUUGCCACCCCCAGUUCCUAUGACACAGUUAUCAAAAAGUAUUAUCAUUGCUCCCCUGAUAGAAGAUUGUUGGUGAAUUUUCAAGGCCUUCAGUUUAUUUCCACUAUUUUCAAAGAAAAUAGAUUAGGUUUGCGGGGGUCUGAGUCUAUGUUCAAAGACUGUGAACAGCUUGCUGUCACUUCUUCACCUCUUCCACUCCUUCUCUCACUGUGUUACUGCUUUGCAAAGACCCGGGAGCUGGCGGGGAACCCUGGGAGUAGCUAGUUUGCUUUUUGCGUACACAGAGAAGGCUAUGUAAACAAACCACAGCAGGAUCGAAGGGUUUUUAGAGAAUGUGUUUCAAAACCAUGCCUGGUAUUUUCAACCAUAAAAGAAGUUUCAGUUGUCCUUAAAUUUGUAUAACGGUUUAAUUCUGUCUUGUUCAUUUUGAGUAUUUUUAAAAAAUAUGUCGUAGAAUUCCUUCGAAAGGCCUUCAGACACAUGCUAUGUUCUGUCUUCCCAAACCCAGUCUCCUCUCCAUUUUAGCCCAGUGUUUUCUUUGAGGACCCCUUAAUCUUGCUUUCUUUAGAAUUUUUACCCAAUUGGAUUGGAAUGCAGAGGUCUCCAAACUGAUUAAAUAUUUGAAGAGA